GAUCUGGCAGCGCCGCGAAGACGAGCGGUCACCGGCGCCCGACCCGAGCGCGCCCAGAGGACGGCGGGGAGCCAAGCCGACCCCCGAGCAGCGCCGCGCGGACCCUGAGGCUCAGAGGGGCAGCUUCAGGGGAGGACACCCCACUGGCCAGGACGCCCCAGGCUCUGCUGCUCUGCCACUCAGCUGCCCUCGGAGGAGCGUACACACCCACCAGGACUGCAUUGCCCCAGCUGUGCAGCCCCUGCCAGAUGUGGGAGGCAGCUAGCUGCCCAGAGGCAUGCCCCCCUGCCAGCCACAGCGACCCCUGCUGCUGUUGCUGCUGCUGCUGGCCUGCCAGCCACAGGUCCCCUCCGCUCAGGUGAUGGACUUCCUGUUUGAGAAGUGGAAGCUCUACGGUGACCAGUGUCACCACAACCUGAGCCUGCUGCCCCCUCCCACGGAGCUGGUGUGCAACAGAACCUUCGACAAGUAUUCCUGCUGGCCGGACACCCCCGCCAAUACCACGGCCAACAUCUCCUGCCCCUGGUACCUGCCUUGGCACCACAAAGUGCAACACCGCUUCGUGUUCAAGAGAUGCGGGCCCGACGGUCAGUGGGUGCGUGGACCCCGGGGGCAGCCUUGGCGUGAUGCCUCCCAGUGCCAGAUGGAUGGCGAGGAGAUUGAGGUCCAGAAGGAGGUGGCCAAGAUGUACAGCAGCUUCCAGGUGAUGUACACAGUGGGCUACAGCCUGUCCCUGGGGGCCCUGCUCCUCGCCUUGGCCAUCCUGGGGGGCCUCAGCAAGCUGCACUGCACCCGCAAUGCCAUCCACGCGAAUCUGUUUGCGUCCUUCGUGCUGAAAGCCAGCUCCGUGCUGGUCAUUGAUGGGCUGCUCAGGACCCGCUACAGCCAGAAAAUUGGCGACGACCUCAGUGUCAGCACCUGGCUCAGUGAUGGAGCGGUGGCUGGCUGCCGUGUGGCCGCGGUGUUCAUGCAAUAUGGCAUCGUGGCCAACUACUGCUGGCUGCUGGUGGAGGGCCUGUACCUGCACAACCUGCUGGGCCUGGCCACCCUCCCCGAGAGGAGCUUCUUCAGCCUCUACCUGGGCAUCGGCUGGGGUGCCCCCAUGCUGUUCGUCGUCCCCUGGGCAGUGGUCAAGUGUCUGUUCGAGAACGUCCAGUGCUGGACCAGCAAUGACAACAUGGGCUUCUGGUGGAUCCUGCGGUUCCCCGUCUUCCUGGCCAUCCUGAUCAACUUCUUCAUCUUCGUCCGCAUCGUUCAGCUGCUCGUGGCCAAGCUGCGGGCACGGCAGAUGCACCACACAGACUACAAGUUCCGGCUGGCCAAGUCCACGCUGACCCUCAUCCCUCUGCUGGGCGUCCACGAAGUGGUCUUCGCCUUCGUGACGGACGAGCACGCCCAGGGCACCCUGCGCUCCGCCAAGCUCUUCUUCGACCUCUUCCUCAGCUCCUUCCAGGGCCUGCUGGUGGCUGUCCUCUACUGCUUCCUCAACAAGGAGGUGCAGUCGGAGCUGCGGCGGCGUUGGCACCGCUGGCGCCUGGGCAAAGUGCUAUGGGAGGAGCGGAACACCAGCAACCACAGGGCCUCAUCUUCGCCCGGCCACGGCCCUCCCAGCAAGGAGCUGCAGUUUGGGAGGGGUGGUGGCAGCCAGGAUUCAUCUGCGGAGACCCCCUUGGCUGGUGGCCUCCCUAGAUUGGCUGAGAGCCCCUUCUGAACCCUGCUGGGACCCCAGCUAGGGCUGGACUCUGGCACCCAGAGGGCGUCGCUGGACAACCCAGAACUGGACGCCCAGCUGAGGCUGGGGGCGGGGGAGCCAACAGCAGCCCCCACCUACCCCCCACCCCCAGUGUGGCUGUCUGCGAGAUUGGGCCUCCUCUCCCUGCACCUGCCUUGUCCCUGGUGCAGAGGUGAGCAGAGGAGUCCAGGGCGGGAGUGGGGGCUGUGCCGUGAACUGCGUGCCAGUGUCCCCACGUAUGUCGGCACGUCCCAUGUGCAUGGAAAUGUCCUCCAACAAUAAAGAGCUCAAGUGGUCA